UGUCUAGUGUGCCCCAGGCUACGAUGGACAGAACUGCUCAAAGGAACUCGAUGCUUGUCAGUCCCAACCCUGUCACAACCAUGGAACCUGUACUCCCAAACCUGGAGGCUUCCACUGUGCCUGCCCUCCAGGCUUUGUGGGGCUACGCUGUGAGGGAGACGUGGACGAGUGUCUGGACCAGCCCUGCCACCCCACAGGCACUGCAGCCUGCCACUCUCUGGCCAAUGCCUUCUACUGCCAGUGUCUGCCUGGACACACAGGCCAGUGGUGUGAGGUGGAGAUAGACCCCUGCCACAGCCAACCCUGCUUUCAUGGAGGGACCUGUGAGGCCACAGCAGGAUCACCCCUGGGUUUCAUCUGCCACUGCCCCAAGGGUUUUGAAGGCCCCACCUGCAGCCACAGGGCCCCUUCCUGCGGCUUCCAUCACUGCCACCACGGAGGCCUGUGUCUGCCCUCCCCUAAGCCAGGCUUCCCACCACGCUGUGCCUGCCUCAGUGGCUAUGGGGGUCCUGACUGCCUGACCCCACCAGCUCCUAAAGGCUGUGGCCCUCCCUCCCCAUGCCUAUACAAUGGCAGCUGCUCAGAGACCACGGGCUUGGGGGGCCCAGGCUUUCGAUGCUCCUGCCCUCACAGCUCUCCAGGGCCCCGGUGUCAGAAACCCGGAGCCAAGGGGUGUGAGGGCAGAAGUGGAGAUGGGGCCUGCGAUGCUGGCUGCAGUGGCCCGGGAGGAAACUGGGAUGGAGGGGACUGCUCUCUGGGAGUCCCAGACCCCUGGAAGGGCUGCCCCUCCCACUCUCGGUGCUGGCUUCUCUUCCGGGACGGGCAGUGCCACCCACAGUGUGACUCUGAAGAGUGUCUGUUUGAUGGCUACGACUGUGAGACCCCUCCAGCCUGCACUCCAGCCUAUGACCAGUACUGCCAUGAUCACUUCCACAACGGGCACUGUGAGAAAGGCUGCAACACUGCAGAGUGUGGCUGGGAUGGAGGUGACUGCAGGCCUGAAGAUGGGGACCCAGAGUGGGGGCCCUCCCUGGCCCUGCUGGUGGUACUGAGCCCCCCAGCCCUAGACCAGCAGCUGUUUGCCCUGGCCCGGGUGCUGUCCCUGACUCUGAGGGUAGGACUCUGGGUAAGGAAGGAUCGUGAUGGCAGGGACAUGGUGUACCCCUAUCCUGGGGCCCGGGCUGAAGAAAAGCUAGGAGGAACUCGGGACCCCACCUAUCAGGAGAGAGCAGCCCCUCAAACGCAGCCCCUGGGCAAGGAGACCGACUCCCUCAGUGCUGGGUUUGUGGUGGUCAUGGGUGUGGAUUUGUCCCGCUGUGGCCCUGACCACCCGGCAUCCCGCUGUCCCUGGGACCCUGGGCUUCUACUCCGCUUCCUUGCUGCGAUGGCUGCAGUGGGAGCCCUGGAGCCCCUGCUGCCUGGACCACUGCUGGCUGUCCACCCUCAUGCAGGGACCGCACCCCCUGCCAACCAGCUUCCCUGGCCUGUGCUGUGCUCCCCAGUGGCCGGGGUGAUUCUCCUGGCCCUAGGGGCUCUUCUCGUCCUCCAGCUCAUCCGGCGUCGACGCCGAGAGCAUGGAGCUCUCUGGCUGCCCCCUGGUUUCACUCGACGGCCUCGGACUCAGUCAGCUCCCCACCGACGCCGGCCCCCACUAGGCGAGGACAGCAUUGGUCUCAAGGCACUGAAGCCAAAGGCAGAAGUUGAUGAGGAUGGAGUUGUGAUGUGCUCAGGCCCUGAGGAGGGAGAGGAGGUGGGCCAGGCUGAAGAAACAGGCCCACCCUCCACGUGCCAGCUCUGGUCUCUGAGUGGUGGCUGUGGGGCGCUCCCUCAGGCAGCCAUGCUAACUCCUCCCCAGGAAUCUGAGAUGGAAGCCCCUGACCUGGACACCCGUGGACCUGAUGGGGUGACACCCCUGAUGUCAGCAGUUUGCUGUGGGGAAGUACAGUCCGGGACCUUCCAAGGGGCAUGGUUGGGAUGUCCUGAGCCCUGGGAACCUCUGCUGGAUGGAGGGGCCUGUCCCCAGGCUCACACCGUGGGCACUGGGGAGACCCCCCUGCACCUGGCUGCCCGAUUCUCCCGGCCAACCGCUGCCCGCCGCCUCCUUGAGGCUGGAGCCAACCCCAACCAGCCAGACCGGGCAGGGCGCACACCCCUUCAUGCUGCUGUGGCUGCUGAUGCUCGGGAGGUCUGCCAGCUUCUGCUCCGUAGCAGACAAACUGCAGUGGACGCUCGCACAGAGGACGGGACCACACCCUUGAUGCUGGCUGCCAGGCUGGCGGUGGAAGACCUGGUUGAAGAACUGAUUGCAGCCCAAGCAGACGUGGGGGCCAGAGAUAAAUGGGGGAAAACUGCGCUGCACUGGGCUGCUGCCGUGAACAACGCCCGAGCCGCCCGCUCGCUUCUCCAGGCCGGAGCCGAUAAAGAUGCCCAGGACAACAGGGAGCAGACGCCGCUAUUCCUGGCGGCGCGGGAAGGAGCGGUGGAAGUAGCCCAGCUACUGCUGGGGCUGGGGGCAGCCCGAGAGCUGCGGGACCAGGCUGGGCUAGCGCCGGCGGACGUCGCUCACCAACGUAACCACUGGGAUCUGCUGACGCUGCUGGAAGGGGCUGGGCCACCAGAGGCCCGUCACAAAGCCACGCCGGGCCGCGAGGCUGGGCCCUUCCCGCGCGCACGGACGGUGUCAGUAAGCGUGCCCCCGCAUGGGGGCGGGGCUCUGCCGCGCUGCCGGACGCUGUCAGCCGGAGCAGGCCCUCGUGGGGGCGGAGCUUGUCUGCAGGCUCGGACUUGGUCCGUAGACUUGGCUGCGCGGGGGGGCGGGGCCUAUUCUCAUUGCCGGAGCCUCUCGGGAGUAGGAGCAGGAGGAGGCCCGACCCCUCGCGGCCGUAGGUUUUCUGCAGGCAUGCGCGGGCCUCGGCCCAACCCUGCGAUAAUGCGAGGAAGAUACGGAGUGGCUGCCGGGCGCGGAGGCAGGGUCUCAACGGAUGACUGGCCCUGUGAUUGGGUGGCCCUGGGAGCUUGCGGUUCUGCCUCCAACAUUCCGAUCCCGCCUCCUUGCCUUACUCCGUCCCCGGAGCGGGGAUCACCUCAACUUGACUGUGGUCCCCCAGCCCUCCAAGAAAUGCCCAUAAACCAAGGAGGAGAGGGUAAAAAAUAGAAGAAUACAUGGUAGGGAGGAAUUCCAAAAAUGAUUACCCAUUAAAAGGCAGGCUGGAAGGCCUUCCUGGUUUUAAGAUGGAUCCCCCAAAAUGAAGGGUUGUGAGUUUAGUUUCUCUCCUAAAAUGAAUGUAUGCCCACCAGAGCAGACAUCUUCCACGUGGAGAAGCUGCAGCUCUGGAAAGAGGGUUUAAGAUGCUAGGAUGAGGCAGGCCCAGUCCUCCUCCAGAAAAUAAGACAGGCCACAGGAGGGCAGAGUGGAGUGGAAAUACCCCUAAGUUGGAACCAAGAAUUGCAGGCAUAUGGGAUGUAAGAUGUUCUUUCCUAUAUAUGGUUUCCAAAGGGUGCCCCUAUGAUCCAUUGUCCCCACUGCCCACAAAUGGCUGACAAAUAUUUAUUGGGCACCUACUAUGUGCCAGGCACUGUGUAGGUGCUGAAAAGUGGCCAAGGGCCACCCCCGCUGAUGACUCCUUGCAUUCCCUCCCCUCACAACAAAGAACUCCACUGUGGGGAUGAAGCGCUUCUUCUAGCCACUGCUAUCGCUAUUUAAGAACCCUAAAUCUGUCACCCAUAAUAAAGCUGAUUUGAAGUGUUA